GGUGCCGGCCGACAAACGACGCGGCGCGGGCGAGUGGGCGGAGGCGGCUGCGGGGAAGGCUGGGCUGCCGCGGGACGCGGUGAAGAUAGCCUGCGGAGUGUCCGGGCUGAACACGGUUGCAGCACUCCCAGUAGACCAGGAGCUCCGGGAGGCAGGGCCGGCCCCACGUCCUCUGCGCACCACCCUGAGUUGGAUCCUCUGUGCGCCACCCCUGAGUUGGAUCCAGGGCUAGCUGCUGUUGACCUCCCCACUCCCACGCUGCCCUCCUGCCUGCAGCCAUGACGCCCCUGCUCACCCUGAUCCUGGUGGUCCUCAUGGGCUUACCUCUGGCCCAGGCCUUGGACUGCCACGUGUGUGCCUACAACGGAGACAACUGCUUCAACCCCAUGCGCUGCCCGGCUAUGGUUGCCUACUGCAUGACCACGCGCACCUACUACACCCCCACCAGGAUGAAGGUCAGUAAGUCCUGCGUGCCCCGCUGCUUCGAGACUGUGUAUGAUGGCUACUCCAAGCACGCGUCCACCACCUCCUGCUGCCAGUACGACCUCUGCAACGGCACCGGCCUUGCCACCCCGGCCACCCUGGCCCUGGCCCCCAUCCUCCUGGCCACCCUCUGGGGUCUCCUCUAAAGCCCCCGAGGCAGACCCACUCAAGAACAAAGCUCUCGAGACACACUGCUACACCCUCGCACCCAGCUCACCCUGCCUCACCCUCCACACUCCCUGCGACCUCCUCAGCCAUGCCCAGGGUCAGGACUGUGGGCAAGAAGACACCCGACCUCCCCCAACCACCACACGACCUCACUUCGAGGCCUUGACCUUUCGAUGCUGUGUGGGAUCCCAAAAGUGUCCGGCUUUGAUGGGCUGAUCAGCCCCUCGCCUGUCCAGGGCUAUUUAUGGGGAGGGGCCCAGUCAGGCAGGGAGCACUGAGCAGAUGGGAGCUGUGGCCAAGCCCACCUUCUGGGAAGCCCUAGGAGAGGCCCCUGCCUCAGUCUGCCCCUGGUGUGCUGGGGCAGGGGGAAGACAAGGAAUGCCCGCAGGUGGGGUGGUGGGGAGACUCUUAGGAGGAAAGGCUCCUCCAGGCCUAGUCACGCUUCCUACUGAGGCCAGGAGCUGCCAGGACCGGUACGGGAUCAGGGCUGUGGGAGGAGGGCCUUUGGCACCGGCCCCUGUGCUAGGAAGUCUGCCAGGCCCGAGUUGGAGCCACCCCCUGCAGGGGAGGGGGCGGCUCUGCCUCAGCAGGCCCCAGGGCCCCCGAAGUCACAGAAGCUUUUUCGGGUCCAGCAAGGGGUGUGUGUCCUCUCAGUCAAACCCCUUGACGUUUCCCACCCCCUCACGGGGAGGGCACCAGGCCUGAAGCUGGCAGGAGCUAGGGCCAUGCUAUAUUUGGUGGGUCCUGGACGCUGACCCGGCCAGCGCUAUUCUGGGCAGGGAGGGAAAGGGGCAGAGCAGGUGGUCCCCCGAGUCCUGGUCCCCAACCACAGCAGGACCCAGCCGAGCAAGGCAAAAGACGCAGGACUGGGGGAUGCGCGCACAGGCUGGGGGUUGGGAGCAGCCUGGGGCCGGCGCGGGCCUGGGCGUGGGAAGGCGGAGCAUGCCACCCUCUCGUGGCCGUGCGGGGGCGGGAGUGGGGAGGGUGGGGUGGGGAGGGCGGAGACCCAGCCCCUCCCCCGCAGCGGGAUGCGCACAGUGAGUGGGUCCCUCCAUCACCUUCCACCUGGGGAUGCACCCACUGGGAGGGCAGGGUGGAAGCCCCAGCUGGGUGUGUGGACUCCCAGGGACCCCACCCCAGGCCUGGGAAGCAGGGGUCAGCCCAACACGCACCAAUCCAUCCCCGAUGCAGGUAGCCCAGGGAGCACCUGCCCCUGCUGUGAAUGGGGCAUUCGGGGGCGUGAGACCUUUUGGUGCCAGCGGUCACGCUGCACCUGAGGCCCCCACCUGACCAGUGCUCCCAGCUCUGGUGUCCUGAGAAACCCUUCAAGCCAUCCCGCAUGGGCAGGAUGGUGACAUAUCCAUGUGGUAGGAUUGUCCCGGCCCCAAAGUAUGGCCCUGGUCAGGGGAGCCCCUGCUGGAAAUUGCAUCUCCAGAGCUUUGAUGCAGGACCCCUGGGGGAUCAGGGAAUGAGGGUCUCCACCCCAGGGGUCUCCUUGCAGUGAGUCUAUAUGCAGGCCUGCGUUCUGCUCCUGGGGCUGGUUCUGAGUGCCCAGCUUCAGUCUCCUGAGAACAUGAGGAUGGGAGGGGGCAGAGUCUUGCUGAGGGCACACCCAGUUCCCGCUGGAGGAGGACAGUGCCAGUCUUCUGCAAAGGGACCUUGGGUGGGAACGGGCCCGGAGCGGGAGGAACGUGACUCCCCAGAGGGAAGAUGGGCAUCAUACUGGGCCCAGAGCUGGGAAGGAGUUGCUGCCAGCACAGGGUGGGCCUGGACUCCCCUCGCCCCUACCCCCAGUGGUUGUGGCUGUAGCCCUAAGCCUGGAGAGCAGGACCGGCCCGGGGUGUCUGGGAGGCUGCCAGGUGCCUCCCAGAGCUCCCAAGGGCCCCCACCUGCAAGUGCCAGCCUCAGGGCAGUGCCCAAAUGAGGCCCUCUCAGCUGCAGCCAGCGAUGCCUUGGGAUGCUUACCGGGAGGGAGGCGGCUUUGGGCUCCUAAGUCCUUGGGAGAGGCUGGGAGCAGUCACUGCGCGGCUUGCGCAAGCCCAUUGUCGGGUUGGGUGGCUUCCUCAGCCAGGGCUGGGAGGGACUCCAGGAUCAGGUCCUCCCUGUCUCGAGUCUCAGUGGGGUGAUGGGGAGGAGACCUGGCCACCCAUGGCUCAGGGGCAGCUGAGAACAAGGACCUGCUGGAGCUGGAAGUGCUGUGGUGUUGAGGGGUGGGGUGGGCAGCUUCUCACACCUGCCUCCUGCCUCCUUCUGUCCACCUUUCCACCACCCUGACCUGUCCCAGCCCCACACAUGGUUCUGCCUGGCUGGCCUGCCCUUGGCACCUGGCGUAGAGCACACAGAAGGCACUCAGCUAAUGCUGGGCAGGCCCACUCAUGGGGAGUGCGUGGCUGUGCAGCACCAGGGAACCGGCACAGCAGCGCCGGCAGAAAUCACAGCAGUAAACUUGUCCGGGUUGUAUGCAUCAAGGUGGCGAUGGACGUGGGUCCCCCCACUGCACUGUGGCCCUGAGCACUGUAUAGCAGCCCGGCAAUGGGAGCCAUUAUCUUGCCCCUUUGACAGAGGAGGACACAGAGGCACAGGGAGGUGAAGUAGCUGCCCCACACUAGUGCCUCCUCGCUCACUCACCACCCCCUGCACCACAGUGCAGCCGCUUCUCCCACCAGCUGGGGUUCCUUGGACCCCCAAGCCUGGGAAGGGGGAGGUGAGUUUACAAAAUGGAAAGCUUAAAAGGAGAAAAGUGGAACCAGAGGUUUGAGAAGCCCUGAGUGGUAGAGUAAGGCCUCCAGCGCUGCCUCUGGGUGCAGGGCAGAGUGGCAGAGGAGAGGGGGAGAGGCACUGGGCACCAUGGGGGCCCAGUUCCCACUUCGGGGAUCUCUCUCGCAGAACCGAGGGUCCCCUUCAUGGGGGUAGAUGCCCAGGGCUAGCUGUUGCCACUGUCUGUGUGGACCUGAGUCCUGGACAUGCCCGAGUGACUCAGGAGUGGCUGCUUGGGCGGGCUCUGUCACCCUAGGAUGUUAUACAUUCUGGGAACUGGACAGGAGUGGCUGCUUGGGCGGGCUCUGGCACCCUGGGAUGUUAUACAUUCUGGGAACUGGACAGGAGUGGCUGCUUGGGUGGGCUCUGGCACCCUGGGAUGUUAUACAUUCUGGGAACUGCAAUCAGCCACUAGAGAAGUCGGAGCUACAGGAAGUGACCCUGGGGUGGGACCUGGGGACAUGGCCAGGUCAGCAUGGGGACACCCGGCUCCAGCAGGAGCUCUGGUCUGUCCUGGGGUCUUUGGGGGCAGGGCUGCGGCCCUGGGCAGGCUUCCUCCAGGCGGAGGUCCUGGGGAAGUGGGGGAGCCAGGCCAGCUGCCGCCUCCCCCACUAUGUAGCAUCUGAUUCGUCAUCUCUCAUGAAGGCGAUUUGGUUCAUAACUCUGAAACUCUGAAAAAGGUCAAAAGAAGCAGAGAGGCCCUCGGUGGAUAUGCCAGCUUUUCUGCCGGUGCUUUCUCCCACUACUCUGGGUGGUCUGCUCUCCUCUUCAAACCUCAGCUCGCAGGGAGGGCCUGAAUCUGCCAGCCCCUCAGGAUCUCCUUCCCUCUGGGCCCUCCCCAGCCUUAAGGAGCCUCCCAGACAGAAGGGUGGACAGAGCCACCUGGGCAGCCCGAGAGACACACGGGGGUCCUCCCUGUGGACAGCCCUGCCAGCUUCCGCCCAGCCCUGAGCUUCAUUUGCAUCUUGAGGAGUAAGGGGUGGUGAAAUGGGAAUGCUGGUCUGGCUCAGCUGGUCGUGGGCAUAAGUGCCCGCUGAAUGGAUGGCAUCUCUCCCUCCUGUCUUAUGUUCUGGGGUCCAGGUGCUUCCCAGGGCCAUGCCCCUGCUGCUAAUGCUUGCCCUAACCCUUACCCUAACCAGCGUCCAGCGUCGUCUCACCGAGCCGUAAAUAAAUCAACAGAUUCGCA